CUUCUGCUCCUGACUCUCGGUGGUGAGGGGCUGCCCUACGGUGGUUCCCUUAAUUGUGGGCCGCCCCCCAUCCUUGCUGCUGGCUGUGGCACCUCGCUCUGUGGGCUGGUGCCCUCACUGUGCUGCUCUUUGAGAACACUCCCUGUCCCAAAUCUGAGUUGGGAAGUUCUCCUGUGUUCCAUCUGCACGGUGGAUGGAGAGUCCCUUUGUCUUCCCAAUUAAACACCCUAGCCAAGAACCCUGAAGUCCUCCCUGCCCCCACCCAUGUCCGCCUUUUCUUUGGCUUUGGCUUUGGUGAGCUCCCCGCAGCCACCGCCACCCAUUGGAAUGGCCAACAGGGGACCUGCAUAUGGCCUGAGCCGGGAGGUGCAGCAGAAGAUUGAGAAACAAUAUGAUGCAGAUCUGGAGCAGAUCCUGAUCCAGUGGAUCACCACCCAGUGCCGAAAGGAUGUGGGCCGGCCCCAGCCUGGACGCGAGAACUUCCAGAACUGGCUCAAGGAUGGCACGGUGCUAUGUGAGCUCAUUAAUGCACUGUACCCCGAGGGGCAGGCCCCAGUAAAGAAGAUCCAGGCCUCCACCAUGGCCUUCAAGCAGAUGGAGCAGAUCUCUCAGUUCCUGCAAGCAGCUGAGCGCUAUGGCAUUAACACCACUGACAUCUUCCAAACUGUGGACCUCUGGGAAGGAAAGAACAUGGCCUGUGUGCAGCGGACGCUGAUGAAUCUGGGUGGGCUGGCAGUAGCCCGAGAUGAUGGGCUCUUCUCUGGGGAUCCCAACUGGUUCCCUAAGAAAUCCAAGGAGAAUCCUCGGAACUUCUCGGAUAACCAGCUGCAAGAGGGCAAGAACGUGAUCGGGUUACAGAUGGGCACCAACCGCGGGGCGUCUCAGGCAGGCAUGACUGGCUACGGGAUGCCACGCCAGAUCCUCUGAUCCCACCCCAGGCCUUGCCCCUGCCCUCCCACGAAUGGUUAAUAUAUAUGUAGAUAUAUAUUUUAGCAGUGACAUUCCCAGAGAGCCCCAGAGCUCUCAAGCUCCUUUCUGUCAGGGUGGGGGGUUCAGCCUGUCCUGUCACCUCUGAGGUGCCUGCUGGCAUCCUCUCCCCCAUGCUUACUAAUACAUUCCCUUCCCCAUAGCCAUCAAAACUGGACCAACUGGCCUCUUCCUUUCCCCUGGGACCAAAAUUUAGGGGCCUCAGUCCCUCACCGCCAUGCCCUGGCCUAUUCUGUCUCUCCUUCUUCCCCCUGGCCUGUUCUGUCUCUGAGCUCUGUGUCCUCCGUUCAUUCCAUGGCUGGGAGUCACUGAUGCUGCCUCUGCCUUCUGAUGCUGGACUGGCCUUGCUUCUACAAGUAUGCUUCUCCCACAGCUGUGGCUGCAGGAACUUAAUUUAUAGGGAGGAGCCUGUGGCAGCUGCUGCCCCAGCCACAGCUGCACUGACUGUGCUCACCACACAUCUGGGGCAGCCUUCCCUGGCAGGGGCCCUCGUGGCUUCUCAUUUUCCAUUCCCUUCACUGUGGCUAAGGGGUGGGGUGAGGGGAUGGAGAGGGAGGGCUGCCUACCAUGGUCUGGGGCUUGAGGAAGAUGAGUUUGUUGAUUUAAAUAAAGAAUUUGUCAUUUUUGAA